AGUCGGACGCGGCGCUGGAAAUCCGGCGGAGGACCUAGAAGUAGCGGGAGCGAUCUGUGGGCGGGGCGAACGGCCUGCCGGCCGACGGUAGGGCCUGAAGAGCCUAGGGCUCCCACAUCAGGACGAGAAGGAGCCCUCGAGUUACCGUGGGAGCUGUGGGAGCUGCCCUGUGACUCUUAGGAAGAUGCCGUACCUUGGCUCCGAGGACGUGGUGAAGGAGCUGAAGAAGGCUCUGUGCAAUCCUCACAUUCAAGCUGAUAGGCUGCGCUACCGGAAUGUCAUCCAGCGAGUGAUUAGGUACAUGACUCAAGGCUUGGACAUGUCUGGUGUUUUUAUGGAAAUGGUGAAGGCCAGUGCCACUGUAGAUAUUGUCCAGAAGAAGUUGGUUUAUCUGUACAUGUGCACAUAUGCUCCCCUGAAACCAGAUCUGGCUCUCCUGGCCAUCAAUACGCUGUGCAAAGACUGCUCAGACCCCAAUCCAAUGGUGCGAGGGCUGGCGUUACGGAGCAUGUGUAGCCUCAGGAUGCCUGGUGUGCAGGAGUAUAUACAACAGCCUAUUCUCAAUGGUCUGCGGGAUAAGGCUUCAUAUGUCAGGAGAGUGGCAGUCCUUGGAUGUGCCAAGAUGCAUAAUCUUCAUGGAGACUCUGAAGUAGAUGGUGCCCUGGUAAAUGAAUUAUACAGUUUGCUGCGUGACCAGGAUCCAAUUGUAGUUGUGAACUGCUUGAGGUCUCUAGAGGAAAUUCUGAAACAGGAAGGAGGCGUUGUCAUCAAUAAGCCCAUUGCUCACCAUCUCUUAAAUCGAAUGUCAAAACUGGACCAAUGGGGCCAGGCUGAAGUAUUGAACUUUCUGCUACGCUACCAACCCCGCAGUGAGGAAGAACUAUUUGACAUUCUCAAUCUGUUGGAUAGUUUCCUCAAGAGCAGUAGCCCAGGUGUGGUGAUGGGAGCUACCAAACUUUUUCUGAUCUUGGCAAAAAUGUUUCCCCACGUACAAACUGAUGUCCUUGUGCGGGUCAAGGGACCUUUGCUAGCUGCCUGUUCUUCAGAGAGCCGUGAGCUCUGUUUUGUUGCUCUUUGUCAUGUACGCCAGAUCUUGCAUAGUUUACCAGGUCACUUUAGCAGCCACUACAAAAAGUUUUUUUGCUCCUACUCGGAGCCCCACUACAUCAAACUACAGAAAGUGGAGGUGCUGUGUGAACUGGUGAACGAUGAGAAUGUGCAGCAGGUGCUAGAGGAGCUUCGAGGGUACUGCACGGAUGUGUCUGCGGACUUUGCACAGGCUGCCAUCUUUGCCAUAGGUGGCAUUGCCAGGACUUACACAGAUCAAUGUGUUCAGAUUUUAACAGAGUUGCUGGGUCUUCGACAAGAGCACAUUACCACAGUGGUGGUGCAGACUUUCCGAGACCUGGUUUGGUUGUGUCCUCAGUGUACUGAAGCUGUAUGUCAGGCCCUGCCCGGCUGUGAAGAGAACAUUCAAGAUAGUGAGGGGAAGCAAGCACUUAUUUGGCUACUUGGUGUCCAUGGGGAAAGAAUUCCUAAUGCUCCUUAUGUGUUAGAGGACUUUGUUGAGAAUGUGAAGUCGGAAACAUUUCCAGCUGUUAAGAUGGAGCUGCUCACUGCUUUGCUGCGCCUUUUCCUCUCCCGACCUGCUGAGUGCCAGGACAUGCUAGGACGUUUGUUGUAUUACUGCAUAGAGGAAGAAAAAGAUAUGGCUGUACGGGACCGAGGUCUCUUCUAUUAUCGCCUCCUCUUAGUUGGCAUUGAUGAAGUUAAGCGGAUUCUGUGUAGCCCUAAAUCUGACCCUACUCUUGGACUUUUGGAGGAUCCGGCAGAAAGACCUGUGAAUAGCUGGGCCUCAGACUUCAACACACUGGUGCCAGUGUAUGGCAAAGCCCACUGGGCAACUAUCUCUAAAUGCCAGGGGGCAGAGCGUUGUGACCCAGAGCUUCCUAAAACUUCAUCCUUUGCCGCAUCAGGACCCUUGAUUCCUGAAGAGAACAAGGAGAGGGUACAAGAACUCCCUGAUUCUGGAGCCCUCAUGCUAGUCCCCAAUCGCCAGCUUACUGCUGAUUAUUUUGAGAAAACUUGGCUUAGCCUUAAAGUUGCUCAUCAGCAAGUGUUGCCUUGGCGGGGAGAAUUCCAUCCUGACACCCUCCAGAUGGCUCUUCAAGUAGUGAACAUCCAGACCAUCGCAAUGAGUAGGGCUGGGUCUCGGCCAUGGAAAGCAUACCUCAGUGCUCAGGAUGAUACUGGCUGUCUGUUCUUAACAGAACUGCUAUUGGAGCCUGGAAACUCAGAAAUGCAGAUCUCUGUGAAACAAAAUGAAGCAAGAACGGAGACGCUGAAUAGUUUUAUUUCUGUAUUAGAAACUGUGAUUGGAACAAUUGAAGAAAUAAAAUCAUAACAGAGUCUUGUUGCUUGUCUAGAGUAAGAUGAAUAACUAUUACACUUUCUUAGUCUUUCCUAUUAGAGCUGCCAGUAAGUCCAGAUAAUAUCAGAUACAAAGGAGAGUGGAAAAUCUAGAAAUCAGGAUUCUUAAGUUUUUGGCCAAAGAACAUUGAUUCAUUCCUUUCAUUCCUAUUGGCAAUUGACCCCAUUUUUCAGUGAUGAUGUUGUAGAGGUUAAUGUUGGUAAGGAGAUGCGUUGAGGAUGGGAUUUGGAUUAUUUCCUAAUCAAUUUUAGGAAUUGUGUUAGUAAUUAAAGAUGGCUGAUGUGUGGAAACUGAUAGGGGUCAUCAUUUGUGGGGGUCAUCUUUUCUUCCCUGGAUUAUUAUAGUAAAUUCCUAACUGUUCUCAUAUUUCCAAUCAUGCUUUUAGGCCAGAUUCCAAAGUCCUUAAUGUCAUCUAAAGUACCUCUUUGGUGUCAAGUCUUGCCACUCCCAAAAUGACUUCUUUUCUGGCAGAAGCAAACCAUUUGCAUUGCAGUUCCCUUUAUACACCUGCUUCUUUCACCUCUGUGUUAACUUAAACCUGCUUUUAUUUAUUGCCUGGAACAUUUUCUCACCCUCAUAUCUUCUUGAAUUAACACCUCGUCUAUCUUUCAGUGUUCAGCUCACUCAUAAGCUCCUUCAGGAAGUUUCCUUUAACCCUCACUGCCUUCAUUAGGGGCCUCCCUCAAGCUAUCAAAGUAGCCAGAGCAUACCUCUAGCAGUAGUAUUGUAAUUGUUUUCUUGUUGCUUGUCCUCAAUUUUUAUUCUGUUCUUAUCUGACCACAUUUUGUACAUUGAAGCAACUUAUGGCAAGAACAAAUCUAAUAAAAUGAUGGUAAAAUAUAAA